AUUAGCUCCAUUCAAGCCUACAAAUUGCAUCACCCUCCUCCUCUGCCCAGACCUGGGGGCUCCAACACCUUUCGCUAGGUCUGGCUCUGGCCUCUGAGCGAACCUUCCGUACAGUAUGGCGGCUCCCGAAGCCCCGCCCCUGGACAGAGUUUUCCGUACAACAUGGCUGUCUACAGAGUGCGAUUCCCACCCACUUCCGCCUAGCUACCGGAAGUUUCUAUUUGAAACCCAGGCGGCCGACUUAGCCGGUGGCACGACAGUUGCUGCAGGGAAUCUUUUAAACGAGAGCGAGAAGGACUGCGGGCAGGACCGGCGGGCUCCUGGGGUUCAGCCGUGCCGCCUCGUUACGAUGACCAGUGUGGUUAAGACAGUGUAUAGCCUGCAGCCCCCCUCUGCGCUGAGCGGCGGCCAGCCGGCAGACACACAAACUCGGGCCACUUCUAAGAGUCUCUUACCUGUUAGGUCCAAAGAAGUCGAUGUUUCCAAACAGCUUCAUUCAGGAGGUCCAGAGAAUGAUGUUACAAAAAUCACCAAACUGAGACGAGAGAAUGGGCAAAUGAAAGCUACUGACACUGCCACCAGAAGGAAUGUCAGAAAAGGCUACAAACCACUGAGUAAGCAAAAAUCAGAGGAAGAGCUCAAGGACAAGAACCAGCUGUUAGAAGCCGUCAACAAGCAGUUGCACCAGAAGUUGACUGAAACUCAGGGAGAGCUGAAGGACCUGACCCAGAAGGUAGAGCUGCUGGAGAAGUUUCGGGACAACUGUUUGGCAAUUUUGGAGAGCAAGGGCCUUGAUCCAGCUUUAGGCAGUGAGACCCUGGCAUCACGACAAGAAUCCACUACUGAUCACAUGGACUCUAUGUUGCUGUUAGAAACUUUGCAAGAGGAGCUGAAGCUUUUUAACGAAACAGCCAAAAAGCAGAUGGAGGAGUUACAGAUUGCUUGGAUGAAUCAUGGGAUAUUGCACCAAAUGUAGAGGAUUUCAUCGUUCCAGUUUAGAUACAGGAGUCUAGUCCCUCUCUACUACUAGAGGGACAAUUCCUAAAACCAGUGCAUAGAAAUAAAAUCUAAAAUAGAAGAUACAGUCUGUUGAUACUCCAGUGGUCUUCCUUAGUGGAAUAGGAGCAUAAUGUUCUGAUGUGGGAAUUGUGUUUCCUGUUAGUCAAGAGUUUUGUGUAUGUGUUGUUUUCUUUUGGAAUGUCUUUCCAUGCAGGCCUUAAAGGUAAAGCUGGAGAUGAAAGAGGAAAGAGUCCGAUUCCUAGAACAGCAAACCUUAUGUAACAAUCAAGUAAAUGAUUUAACAACAGCCCUUAAGGAAAUGGAGCAGCUAUUAGAAAUGUAAGAAGAAGCAAGUGGCCAGAUGGCUCCCUCUUGGGCAUAAAAUCUCAGAGGAAGCUACUUAGGACAUCAUCUUGGCCAUGAUCUUCUGGGACUCACCAUCUCCAGAAUGAAAACAAUUUCUACAGUAGACUUAAGGACAGUUUAUGCUGAAAUGGCAAUUCCUCAUUUAAGCAAGUUUUCCCAACCUUCAGGUUGGUCAGCCCUCCUGAGCCUCACAGGUGGAUAAUUGAGGCCUACAAGAGAGGGGAGCCUAGGAGCUUGGAUUGACCUUCUAGUCAACCACCUGACUUCAGCACACCAUUACAAUCGGGAGACUAAACCAACAACCAGAGGAUCUAAAAUGUCACAUUCAGAUUUUCAGGAAGAAAAUCUUCAUUACAGUGGAGCACAAAUGUUCCAUACAAGACAUCAUUGAGGAGCCAUGCUGUCCCCUUCUAACCUGAAACACAUUCUUUCCCAUCCUGGUUGGGCUUCUGUACCUCCUUAUUAAUUUAUGAACCUGAAGUUGCUUGAAGUGUUUUGGGCUUAAUAAAUGGGGUGAAAGUAUAGGUAGCAGUAACACCUACAUGAAACAAUACACCUUGGAUCUUUUAAUCUAAAUUACUUUUCUUUUUUAAGUCUACUUUUAAAAUAAAUACUUCUGUAAAUAUUCUGACUGUAACAUUGAGGAAUGAAAAUAGCCUUUUAACCUA